GCCAUCUUGCGAGCUCGUCGUACUGACCGAGCGGGGAGGCUGUCUUGAGGCGGCACCGCUCACCGACACCGAGGCGGACUGGCAGCCCUGAGCGUCGCAGUCAUGCCGGCCGGACCCGUGCAGGCGGUGCCCCCGCCGCCGCCCGUGCCCACGGAGCCCAAACAGCCCACAGAAGAAGAAGCAUCUUCAAAGGAGGAUUCUGCACCUUCUAAGCCAGUUGUGGGGAUUAUUUACCCUCCUCCAGAGGUCAGAAAUAUUGUUGACAAGACUGCCAGCUUUGUGGCCAGAAACGGGCCUGAAUUUGAAGCUAGGAUCCGACAGAACGAGAUCAACAACCCCAAGUUCAACUUUCUGAACCCCAAUGACCCUUACCAUGCCUACUACCGCCACAAGGUCAGCGAGUUCAAGGAAGGGAAGGCUCAGGAGCCGUCCGCCGCCAUCCCCAAGGUCAUGCAGCAGCAGCAGCAGACCACCCAGCAGCAGCUGCCCCAGAAGGUCCAAGCCCAAGUAAUCCAAGAGACCAUCGUGCCCAAAGAGCCUCCUCCUGAGUUUGAGUUCAUUGCUGAUCCUCCCUCUAUCUCAGCCUUCGACUUGGAUGUGGUGAAGCUGACGGCUCAGUUUGUGGCCAGGAAUGGGCGCCAGUUUCUGACCCAGCUGAUGCAGAAAGAGCAGCGCAACUACCAGUUUGACUUUCUCCGCCCACAGCACAGCCUCUUCAACUACUUCACGAAGCUAGUGGAACAGUACACCAAGAUCUUGAUUCCACCCAAAGGUUUAUUUUCAAAGCUCAAGAAAGAGGCUGAAAACCCCCGAGAAGUUUUGGAUCAGGUGUGUUACCGAGUGGAAUGGGCCAAAUUCCAGGAACGUGAGAGGAAGAAGGAAGAAGAGGAGAAGGAGAAGGAGCGGGUGGCCUAUGCUCAGAUCGACUGGCAUGAUUUUGUGGUGGUGGAAACAGUGGACUUCCAACCCAAUGAGCAAGGGAACUUCCCUCCCCCCACCACGCCAGAGGAGCUGGGGGCCCGAAUCCUCAUUCAGGAGCGCUAUGAAAAGUUUGGGGAGAGUGAGGAAGUUGAGAUGGAGGUCGAGUCUGAUGAGGAGGAUGACAAACAGGAGAAGGCGGAGGAGCCUCCUUCCCAGCUGGACCAGGACACCCAAGUACAAGAUAUGGAUGAGGGUUCAGAUGAUGAAGAAGAAGGGCAGAAAGUGCCCCCACCCCCAGAGACACCCAUGCCUCCACCUCUGCCCCCAACUCCAGACCAAGUCAUUGUCCGCAAGGAUUAUGAUCCCAAAGCCUCCAAGCCCUUGCCUCCAGCCCCUGCUCCAGAUGAGUAUCUUGUGUCCCCCAUUACUGGGGAGAAGAUCCCCGCCAGCAAAAUGCAGGAACACAUGCGCAUUGGACUUCUUGACCCUCGCUGGCUGGAGCAGCGGGAUCGCUCCAUCCGUGAGAAGCAGAGCGAUGAUGAGGUGUACGCACCAGGUCUGGAUAUUGAGAGCAGCUUGAAGCAGUUGGCUGAGCGGCGUACUGACAUCUUCGGUGUAGAGGAAACAGCCAUUGGUAAGAAGAUCGGUGAGGAGGAGAUCCAGAAGCCAGAGGAAAAGGUGACCUGGGAUGGCCACUCAGGCAGCAUGGCCCGGACCCAGCAGGCUGCCCAGGCCAACAUCACCCUCCAGGAGCAGAUUGAGGCCAUUCACAAGGCCAAAGGCCUGGUGCCAGAGGAUGACACUAAAGAGAAGAUUGGCCCCAGCAAGCCCAAUGAAAUCCCUCAACAGCCACCGCCACCAUCUUCAGCCACCAACAUCCCCAGCUCGGCUCCACCCAUCACUUCAGUGCCCCGACCACCCACAAUGCCACCUCCAGUUCGUACUACAGUUGUCUCCGCAGUACCCGUCAUGCCCCGGCCCCCAAUGGCAUCUGUGGUCCGGCUGCCCCCAGGCUCAGUGAUCGCCCCCAUGCCGCCCAUCAUCCACGCGCCCAGAAUCAACGUGGUGCCCAUGCCUCCCUCGGCCCCUCCUAUUAUGGCCCCCCGCCCACCCCCCAUGAUUGUGCCAACAGCCUUUGUGCCUGCUCCACCUGUGGCACCUGUCCCAGCUCCAGCCCCAAUGCCCCCUGUGCAUCCCCCACCUCCCAUGGAAGAUGAGCCCACCUCCAAAAAACUGAAGACAGAGGACAGCCUCAUGCCAGAGGAGGAGUUCCUGCGCAGAAACAAGGGUCCAGUGUCCAUCAAAGUCCAGGUGCCCAACAUGCAGGAUAAGACGGAAUGGAAACUGAAUGGGCAGGUGCUGGUCUUCACCCUCCCACUCACGGACCAGGUCUCUGUCAUUAAGGUGAAGAUUCAUGAAGCCACAGGCAUGCCUGCAGGGAAACAGAAGCUACAGUAUGAGGGUAUCUUCAUCAAAGAUUCCAACUCACUGGCUUACUACAACAUGGCCAAUGGCGCAGUCAUCCACCUGGCCCUCAAGGAGAGAGGCGGGAGGAAGAAGUAGACAAGAGGAACCUGCUGUCAAGUCCCUGCCAUUUUGCCUCUCCUGUCUCCCACCCCCUGCCCCAGACCCAGGAGCCCCCCUGAGGCUUUGCCUUGCCUGCAUAUUUGUUUCGCUCUUACUCAGUUUGGGAAUUCAAAUUGUCCUGCAGAGGUUCAUUCCCCUGACCCUUUCCCCACAUUGGUAAGAGUAGCUGGGUUUUCUAAGCCACUCUCUGGAAUCUCUUUGUGUUAGGGUCUCGAUUUGAGGACAUUCAUUUCUUCAGCAGCCCAUUAGCAACUGAGAGCCCAGGGAUGUCCUACAGGAUAGUUUCAUAGUGACAGGUGGCACUUGGCUAAUAGAAUAUGGCUGAUAUUGUCAUUAAUCAUUUUGUACCUUGACAUGGGUUGUCUAAUAAAACUCGGACCCUUCUUGUGAAAUCAGUUAAAUAAGACUUGUCUCGGUCACCUGUGCCCUGUCCAGACUCGAGGCAGUGGUAACACUGCACAGUGCUAUGUGGCUUCUCUUUGAGGAUUUUUGGGUUUUGUAACUAAAUUCUUGCUGCCCUCAUACUUUUUAUGUAUUAGAAUCAUAUUCGUAUUGCCCUUUUAAAACAUUGGGAUCCUCCAAAGGCCUGCCCCAUGUAUUUAACAGUAAUACAGGAAGCAUGGCAGGCACCAUGCAAACCAAGGAUGGAUGGUGCAGUCCCUGUGUCAGUGGGCGGUGGUUUCCUGCUGGCCUGGAAUCACUCAUCACCUGAUUGAUUGGCUCUGUGGUCCUGGGCAGGUGCCUCAUAGGUGUGUGGAUAUGAUGACGUUUCUUUAAAAUGUAUGUAUUUAACAAAUACUUAAUUGUAUUAAGGUCAUGUACCAAGGAUUUGAUAAAGUUUAAAUAAUUUACUCUCUACUUUUAUCCAUUUUAUCCAUUUUAACUCAUGUAAUCCUCAUGUGAGUAUUCCUGUUUAACACUUGAGUAAACUGAGGCACAGAGAACAUAAGUUGCAUGCCAUAGUCACACACUGUGAAAGUGAAAAGAGAAUGUGUGCAAAACACGUCACAGUCCUGGUUUCUGAGUAAAGGCAGGCUGUUAUCUUUAGAAUCAAGCUAUCACAGGGAGAUAGGCAAUGCUGUGGGUGUUGGAGGAAGGUGAGAGCCUGUUGCUAACAAUUUCCUGGUUUUAAAGCUAAGGCUGAUUUUAUUGGGAAGAUCUCACAUGUGUGUGGCCCCUGAGAGUUCCCAGUGCCUUUUAUUUGCAGUCCUUCCAUUUGGACCUCCUAGCUGCCCCAUCAGGUCAUCUCCAGGGCUCAGAGGGGUGAGACCAUUUCCCAAGGUCACAGAACCAGCUCUCUAGUCACCACCCUGCCUCUCCCUCUCACCCAGAGUCAGUACCAGUUUUAUGGCUUUAUUACAAACUGCUGGGUCCCUCCCAUUUUCAACUUGAUUGAUGGGAUGUCAUCCCUUAUCCUGUCUGACAUUUGCCUCUGGCCUGGUUGCUAGAAGUUUGCCCCAGGGGCAAGAGUUGAAAUUUGGCUUCCUGAGGUGGGCUUUGUGGUUUGCGUCCCUAAAGUGAGCCCACUACUGGUUGCUUGUCCAUGGCCAACACCAGAAAUCCCCUGAGCACUACCUGGGUCUCAUUCCAAGAAGGAAGAGGGUCAGGAGACCUGGGGAGUCUCAUAUUCCAAGUUCUUCUUUCUUUCUGGGAGCAGUGGGCAGUUCAUGGUGUUAGGGCACUCACCCCCACAGACUGGCAAACCCUGCAGGACUUCCGUGGCUGAGGCUGUGACCGGAGGCCAGGAAUGCCGUUGGGUGGAUUGUGAGUGAAUGGGCCCUUUGAGCUGCCCUCUAGAGAGCAAAUCCAGUUUCCUGGAGCUCCUGAAUGAAUAUCUGUACUGGCUCGCUCAGAUGCAGAAGCUCCAUUGACCAUGAGGCCUUGUGAACAUCAGUGGCCACAGGCCCAGUGUGCUGCUUGGCACUGCACUAGUUUAGGACCUGCAGCAUGUAGGUAGCGUCCUAGUGUUUAUAAUACAAAGCUGCUCUGCACAGCUUUUCUGAUUCUUCUUGCAAUCUCCUGAGGAUUAUCUGCCCCAUUUUUAAAACGAGGUGGAAUACCCAAGGUCAUGUAGCCAGUGAGUGCUCUGGAAAGCCAAAGCAGCUCAUCCCUUCCUGGGGACCACACUGCUCUGCUCCACCAGACCACACUAUGAAAUAGGAAUAAGUGCUCCUGUUGCAGGACUGCUGGGAAAACAGGUGGUGUGGGACUUAAGUCACCAUAAUUUUGAAGACUUGCAUGCAGAGGGCUCCAGGAAUUGUAGACAUUAAGGAAUUUCACUUUCAGUUCUACCCACUACUUAAGUACUUGUCAUGUACUCUUAGAGGAGGCCAGUAAUGAUCAGAACCAUUUUACUUUAAAAUUAAUAAUAUUGUAUUAGAGAAUAUAUUAAAUGGUUAUAUUGGGUUAUGUUAGGAUAUAUACUUGAAUGGAAAUACAUGUACUAUUAGCAAUCAUAUUUCAUUUAUCCCUGUAAUUAGACAAGAAAGCAUAAUAUAGCUCUACUCAUGGGUACACAUACCAGUGUAUAAGAUUUUUAGAAGUUUACUUUUUAAAAAUAAAAGCAAAAUGUAAGAUCUUAA